AUUCGGAUUUGGCGCGAGCGCGGCUGGAGUUUGCUGCUGCCGCUGUGCAGUUUGUUCAGGGGCUUGUGGUGGUGAGUCCGAGAGGCUGCGUGUGAGAGACGUGAGAAGGAUCCUGCACUGAGGAGGUGGAAAGAAGAGGAUUGCUCGAGGAGGCCUGGGGUCUGUGAGGCAGCGGAGCUGGGUGAAGGCUGCGGGUUCCGGCGAGGCCUGAGGUGAAGUGAAGGGAAAAGAGCUGAGCUCGCUGGAGGUCUGAGCUGUGCUGUCGUCAUGCCUCAAACCCGAUCCCAGGCACAGGCUACAAUCAGUUUUCCAAAAAGGAAGCUGUCUCGGGCAUUGAACAAAGCUAAAAACUCCAGUGAUGCCAAACUAGAACCAACAAAUGUCCAAACCGUAACCUGUUCUCCUCGUGUAAAAGCCCUGCCUCUCAGCCCCAGGAAACGUCUGGGCGAUGACAACCUAUGCAACACUCCCCAUUUACCUCCUUGUUCUCCACCAAAGCAAGGCAAGAAAGAGAAUGGUCCCCCUCACUCACAUACACUUAAGGGACGAAGAUUGGUAUUUGACAAUCAGCUGACAAUUAAGUCUCCUAGCAAAAGAGAACUAGCCAAAGUUCACCAAAACAAAAUACUUUCUUCAGUUAGAAAAAGUCAAGAGAUCACAACAAAUUCUGAGCAGAGAUGUCCACUGAAGAAAGAAUCUGCAUGUGUGAGACUAUUCAAGCAAGAAGGCACUUGCUACCAGCAAGCAAAGCUGGUCCUGAACACAGCUGUCCCAGAUCGGCUGCCUGCCAGGGAAAGGGAGAUGGAUGUCAUCAGGAAUUUCUUGAGGGAACACAUCUGUGGGAAAAAAGCUGGAAGCCUUUACCUUUCUGGUGCUCCUGGAACUGGAAAAACUGCCUGCUUAAGCCGGAUUCUGCAAGACCUCAAGAAGGAACUGAAAGGCUUUAAAACUAUCAUGCUGAAUUGCAUGUCCUUGAGGACUGCCCAGGCUGUAUUCCCAGCUAUUGCUCAGGAGAUUUGUCAGGAAGAGGUAUCCAGGCCAGCUGGGAAGGACAUGAUGAGGAAAUUGGAAAAACAUAUGACUGCAGAGAAGGGCCCCAUGAUUGUGUUGGUAUUGGACGAGAUGGAUCAACUGGACAGCAAAGGCCAGGAUGUAUUGUACACGCUAUUUGAAUGGCCAUGGCUAAGCAAUUCUCACUUGGUGCUGAUUGGUAUUGCUAAUACCCUGGAUCUCACAGAUAGAAUUCUACCUAGGCUUCAAGCUAGAGAAAAAUGUAAGCCACAGCUGUUGAACUUCCCACCUUAUACCAGAAAUCAGAUAGUCACUAUUUUGCAAGAUCGACUUAAUCAGGUAUCUAGAGAUCAGGUUCUGGACAAUGCUGCAGUUCAAUUCUGUGCCCGCAAAGUCUCUGCUGUUUCAGGAGAUGUUCGCAAAGCACUGGAUGUUUGCAGAAAGGAGGACUUGUUUCUCAGUGGGGAGCUCUGGAUUUCCACCGUGUUAAUGUCUGAAACAUUAUCAGUCCAUUACCUACAGAGGGAGAAACAAAUGAGAUGUUGCUGGCACUCCCUGUGGAGAGCUAUUGAAAUUGUAGAGUCAGAUGUCAAAAGCCAGACUAUUCUCAAACCACUGUCUGAAUGUAAAUCACCUUCUGAGCCUCUGAUUCCCAAGAGGGUUGGUCUUAUUCACAUAUCCCAAGUCAUCUCAGAAGUUGAUGGUAACAGGAUGACCUUGAGCCAAGAAGGAGCACAAGAUUCCUUCCCUCUUCAGCAGAAGAUCUUGGUUUGCUCUUUGAUGCUCUUGAUCAGGCAGUUGAAAAUCAAAGAGGUCACUCUGGGGAAGUUAUAUGAAGCCUACAGUAAAGUCUGUCGCAAACAGCAGGUGGCGGCUGUGGACCAGUCAGAGUGUUUGUCACUUUCAGGGCUCUUGGAAGCCAGGGGCAUUUUAGGAUUAAAGAGAAACAAGGAAACCCGUUUGACAAAGGUGUUUUUCAAGAUUGAAGAGAAAGAAAUAGAACAUGCUCUGAAAGAUAAAGCUUUAAUUGGAAAUAUCUUAGCUACUGGAUUGCCUUAAAUUCUUCUCUUACACCCCACCCGAAAGUAUUCAGCUGGCAUUUAGAGAGCUACAGUCUUCAUUUUAGUGCUUUACACAUUCGGGCCUGAAAACAAAUAUGACCUUUUUUACUUGAAGCCAAUGAAUUUUAAUCUAUAGAUUCUUUAAUAUUAGCACAGAAUAAUAUCUUUGGGUCUUACUAUUUUUACCCAUAAAAGUGACCAGGUAGACCCUUUUUAAUUACAUUCACUACUUCUACCACUUGUGUAUCUCUAGCCAAUGUGCUUGCAAGUGUACAGAUCUGUGUAGAGGAAUGUGUGUAUAUUUACCUCUUCGUUUGCUCAAACAUGAGUGGGUAUUUUUUUGUUUGUUUUUUUUGUUGUUGUUGUUUUUGAGGCGCGUCUCACCCUGUUGCCCAGGCUGGAGUGCAAUGGCGCGUUCUCUGCUCACUACAGCACCCGCUUCCCAGGUUGAAGUGAUUCUCUUGCCUCAGCCUCCCGAGUAGCUGGGAUUACAGGUGCCCACCACCGCGCCCAGCUAAUUUUUUAAUUUUUAGUAGAGACAGGGUUUUACCAUGUUGGCCAGGCUGGUCUUGAACUCCUGACCCUCAAGUGAUCUGCCCACCUUGGCCUCCCUAAGUGCUGGGAUUAUAGGCGUGAGCCACCAUGCUCAGCCAUUAAGGUAUUUUGUUAAGAACUUUAAGUUUAGGGUAAGAAGAAUGAAAAUGAUCCAGAAAAAUGCAAGCAAGUCCACAUGGAGAUUUGGAGGACACUGGUUAAAGAAUUUAUUUCUUUGUAUAGUAUACUAUGUUCAUGGUGCAGAUACUACAACAUUGUGGCAUUUUAGACUCGUUGAGUUUCUUGGGCACUCCCAAGGGCGUUGGGGUCAUAAGGAGACUAUAACUCUACAGAUUGUGAAUAUAUUUAUUUUCAAGUUGCAUUCUUUGUCUUUUUAAGCAAUCAGAUUUCAAGAGAGCUCAAGCUUUCAGAAGUCAAUGUGAAAAUUCCUUCCUAGGCUGUCCCACAGUCUUUGCUGCCCUUAGAUGAAGCCACUUGUUUCAAGAUGACUACUUUGGGGUUGGGUUUUCAUCUAAACACAUUUUUCCAGUCUUAUUAGAUAAAUUAGUCCAUAUGGUUGGUUAAUCAAGAGCCUUCUGGGUUUGGUUUGGUGGCAUUAAAUGGCAAUUUGUGACUGAGACACCAGAGGGCACCCUUAUAACAUUGACUACUUUGAAAGGGGAUGCUUGAGGCUGAGGUAGUUUUGAGGGAAAGGGGGAAGUUCUAGUUUGAUUUGUUUGGGAGAUUGCUGUCCUUUCAUAACUGAAGCAAAUGCUUGAAAUGUAAACCAUGUGUGAUACGAAUGAUCUGAGAGCCAGUGACCAAGUCUGCUUUUCCCUGAGCUCUCCUGCUGCCGCCUCUACCUUUCUGACAUGGCCUUCCAUUUGGAACUUGAUAUGUGUACAAGUGAUCUGUUGGCCACUGUUUCAUUCAUCCUGACCACUGUAUCCGUGUAAUGUGAUCUGAGCUACAACAGGUGGUAUGGGAUAGAGGCAAGGAAAGCAGAGAGAGCCCUCUGAAAUGAACACUACCCACUGGUGUGUGUAGCACAUGAUAGUCUGUAGGCAUGAGUCUGAAUGUUGUUCUCACACUCCUUUACUAGAGUAUUCGUUCCCUCUGAAGGUAGUUUGAACAUGGAAACACAGUUCUAUACCUAGAAGGUUGGAAAGUGUCUGGGACUAUAAGGGUUAACAUGCAUAAUUGCAAAGAUUGUCCGAAGGCUGAUGGAAAGCAGAGACUGAAUGGGAUUGAGAACAGAUGCGAAGCUUGAUUUAAAUUACAUUUUAUUGGAUGCUGCAGCCUUAAGAGACGUGACUGCUUUACAGUUUGUUUCCACACUGUGGGCAGCUGCUGUCUGUUCUGUGUCCACAGUAGGAUCCUGCCCAAUAAGGAGCAGCCUCCCCACCUCAUUGUGUUUGAGGCUUGGCGCCUUCCUCUUAACUGUAGGGCUUGAGUCAGGAACAUGGCUUGACUCGCAGUGGGGCUGCUAUGUAUCCUCCCUGGCUUCCAGCCAAAAUCACAUUGGUAGAUUCAAAGGGGCCAAAUUUCUUUCCCCUCUAUCUUUCCCUUUCCCCUGGUUUUGGAAAUAGAGUUUUCUGUCUACUGAUUUGUUAGUUUCCUUUUCUUCUCCCCUCACUGUCAAUUUCUAGGUCAUUGCUGCUCUUAAGACUUUAGCAGUUGGAACAGGGUUGGUUCUGUCAAUGAUGCAUGAAGCAGACUUAGUGUCCCUGCUUGGCUUCUGCUGCCCUUGUGGGAGCAAAAGCUGAUAUAUGUUUGUCAGUAAAGUCUUAAGUGUAAUUCAGACUGCUGAGGAAGAAAGCCCUUUCCUUGCUGGCUUUUCUCCCUGAAGCUGAGAGCUUCAGGAAGGUGGUAGGAGUUUUAGUGGGAUGGGAUGGGAUGGGCUUGUGGUUAGCAGUUUUUGCCAGGAUCAUAGGCUGCUUCACUUAGAGUAGUGGCAAAGAUGCUGACCUACAUUCUUCCUUUUGAAGGUGAUGGAGUGUGUGUCUAUAUCCUGGUUUAUCUCUCUCCCCCACCCCAAGGAAGCUGAUUAAGCUUCCAUAGAGUGUUGGGUGUUGCCAUGGAAAGAGCAUAGACAAAAUAAAUUGUGUGUUUCAACCCCA